AUGCCUCUGUUGGCUUCUCCUGGCCCAGCCCCUGCCUGUUGGCGGCCUCUAGAGGCCCAGCCUCUACCUCAACAGUGGGCCCUCCACGCCCACCUCUUUCCUCGCCGUGGCCUCCUCGGGCCAGGCUCCCGCCUUGGGGCGGCCCCCGGAAGCCCAGCUCCUGCCUCACGGCCCUCCGGAGGCCAAGCUCAUGCGUCAGGGCGGCCUCUCCCGGCCUGGCGUUUGCUCCUUUGCAUGGGCUCCAGGUCCUGCACUUCCUCCAGUCGGCCUCUCCAGACCCAGCUCUUCCUCCCAGCAGCCUCUGCAGGACCAGACUGUCGUCAAGUAGGCCUGUCCAGGGACAGCUCCUGCCUCCCGGCGGCCUCUGUAGGCCCAGACUGUCUUCAAGUAGGCCUGUCCAAGGACAGCUCCUGCCUCCCGGAGACCUCUGUAGGCCCAAGUCGUCCUCAAGUCGGCCUCCCCAGGCCCAGCUCCGGCCUCUCGGCGGCCUCUCCAAGUGCAAAAGUUCCUCGAGUCAGUCUCUCCAGGCCCAGGUCCUCCUGUCUCCCAGUGGCCUCUUUCGGCCUAGCCCAGUUCAUGCCUCCUGGUGGCCUUCCCAGGCCCCACUUUUGACUUUCCGCAGCCUCUGCAGAUUCCGAACUUGACCUCCAGUCGGCCUCUCCAGGCCCGGCCUCCUGCCUCCCGAAGGCCUGCACAGGGCCAGUCUCUGCCUCACAGUGGGCUCUCCACCCCCAGCUAGCUCUCGCCUCACUGCAGCCUCCCAAGUCCAAAUCUCCUGCCUCUUGGCCGCUUCGGCAGGCCCAGCUCCCACCUGCCAGUGGCCUCUUCAGGCCCAUGGGGCUCAUUCCUCACAACGGCCUUUCCAGGCCCAUUUUUUCCCGUCCGACUGCCUCUCAGGACCCAGAACCUCUGGGCCCACUUGAGGAGAUGCAGCCAGGAGGAACAGCUGGGCUUGCAGAGGCUGCCAUGAGGGAGGCAGAGGCUGGGCCUCCUGAAGUCGGCCUCUCCAGACCCACUUGCAGCCUCCCGGCGUCCUCUCCGGGCUCAGCUCUUCCUCCCGGCUGCGUCUCCAGGCCCGACUCCGGCCUCCCAACAACCUCUUUGGACUCAGCUCCCGCCCAACUCCCGGUGGCCCUGGUUGGCCCACAACUUCCUGAAGCCAAGCUCCCCAGGCCCAGCUCAGGCCUCACGGUGGCCUCUCUAGGCUCAGCUCCUGCCCUCCGACGGUGUCUCCAGGCCCCGAACGGCCUCCAGUCGGUGGAUUCCUCUAUGCCCAGCUUGGGCCUCCCGGCGGCCUCUGCUGGCCCAAAUCGUCCUGAAGUCGCCCUCUCCAGGCCCAGCUCCGGCCUCCCGGCGGCCUCUCCAGGCGCAACGCAUCGUCAACGAGGGCCCCUCCGGGGCCAGCUCCUGCCUCUCGUCAGCCUCUAGAGACCCAGCCUCUGCCUCCCGCAUGGCGGCCUCUGCAGGCCCAGACUGCCCUUGAGUCAGGCUCUCCAGGGCCAGCUCCAGCCUCCCGGCAGACUCUGCAGGCCCAAGUCAUCCUCAAGUCGGCCUGGAAGUGGGCCUGGAAGAGCUGCACGUUGGCCUCCCCGGGCCCAGCUCCGUCCUCUCGGCGGCCUCUCCAGGUGCAAAACUUCCUCGAGUCAGCCUCUCCAGGUCCAGCUCCUCCUGCCUCCCAGUGGCCUCUUUCAGUCCAGCCCAGCUCGUGGCUGUAGGCAGCCUUCCCAGGCCCUGCUUUUGACUUUUGGCGGCCUCUUCAGGCCCAGAACUUGAUCUCCAGUCAGCUUUUGCAGGCCCGGCAUCCUGCCUCCCGAAGGCCUCUUUCAGCCCAGCCCAGCUCGUGGCUGUAGGCAGCCUUCCCAGGCCCUGCUUUUGACUUUUGGUGGCCUCUUCAGGCCCAGAACUUGAUCUCCAGUCAGCUUUUGUAGGCCCGGCAUCCUGCCUCCCGAAGGCCUGCACGGGCCCGGCCUCGGAAUCACAGCAGACUCUCCACGCCCAGCUAGCUCUCACCUCACUGUGGCCUCCCCAGUCCAAAGCUCCUGCCUUUCGGCCGCUUCGGCAGGCCCAGCUCCCGCCUGCCAGUGGCCUCUUUAGGCCCAGCUCAUUCCUCACAAUGGCCUUUCCAGGCCCCAUUUUUCCCUUCCGGCAGCCUCUUGGCCUCUAAUUUUUUUUAUCUUUUGUGUAUAAAUCCCAAAAUAUGGAAUUUUGGAAUAUUUCCACCAUUAUAUAAAUAUUUUGGUAGGUAAUUUAUUUGGAGUGAGUUUCUGCACCAAGCCCGAAUUUUUUAUUUUAUUUUCCUUAUUAUUUGGUGUUAAACAGGUUUAAUGACAGUCAUGGCAACUUUUUGGCACAAUAGAAAAUAUCGCCCAUGAUCAACGUGUUCUGUUCUGGGGAAGGGGGCAAAGGCAGGGUGAAUCACUUUCUUAAAAAGUACAACUCAAGUUGGGAGUGCAGAGGGAAUCGGGAGAAAACCCUCCCGCUGCCUGUGUCGAAGUGCAGGAGCCCCCACCCCCAUACUCACCUGAGUCCAGCCCCUCUGGAGAAAGAAGGGGUGCAUGAACUCCCCCUAUUCCACAGGCACCUCCCUGUGGCCCAAGGCCCUCUUCACACUCCAUCUUGUAGCCCCAGCAGGAGCUAUUUUCCGAAAAGUGAAAAGCUCUGAAGGUCCCACACUUCAUGGUAUGUACAGGGGCUCAGAGGAGGGAAACUGCCCAGCUUUCCCCCGGCACAGCUGCAGGGGUAGGGGGUAUAUAUAAGAGGAGCAGGCCUU